CUUCUCGAUCGUGUCAGUUUGUAAGGCGAGGGCGGAAGUUGGAUUCCUGGCCUGAGAAUAUUAGGCGUAGUUUUCCAGUUUUUGGCAAAGCGGAAAUACUUAAGGCCCCUGGGUUGACUGGGUUCUUUGUUUUAUCUACCGGCUUCUGCUUUACGACAGGUCACAAACAUGUCAGACAAAAGUGAAUUAAAGGCUGAGUUGGAACGUAAGAAGCAGCGACUGGCCCAAAUCAGAGAGGAAAAGAAGAGAAAAGAAGAAGAAAGGAAAAAAAAAGAAACAGACCAGAAGAAGGAAGCUGUUGCUCCUGUGCAAGAAGAAUCAGAUCUUGAAAAAAAAAGGAGAGAAGCUGAAGCAUUGCUUCAAAGCAUGGGGCUAACUCCAGAAUCCCCCAUUGUUUUUUCUGAAUACUGGGUCCCUCCUCCUAUGUCUCCAUCCUCCAAAUCUGUGAGCACUCCAAGUGAAGCUGGAAGCCAAGACUCUGGAGAUGGCGCCGUGGGAUCUAGGACGCUGCAUUGGGAUACAGAUCCAUCAGUUCUUCAGCUUCACUCAGAUUCCGAUUUGGGACGAGGACCUAUUAAACUUGGAAUGGCUAAAAUCACGCAAGUCGACUUUCCUCCUCGAGAAAUUGUCACGUAUACAAAGGAAACUCAGACUCCAGUUAUGGCUCAACCCAAAGAAGAUGAAGAGGAAGAUGAUGAUGUAGUGGCUCCUAAACCACCUAUUGAACCUGAAGAAGAGAAAACUUUAAAGAAAGAUGAGGAAAAUGAUAGUAAAGCUCCCCCUCAUGAGCUGACUGAAGAAGAAAAGCAACAAAUCUUGCACUCUGAGGAAUUUUUAAGUUUCUUUGACCAUUCUACAAGAAUUGUAGAAAGAGCUCUUUCUGAGCAGAUUAACAUCUUCUUUGACUAUAGUGGGAGAGAUUUGGAAGACAAAGAAGGAGAGAUUCAAGCAGGUGCUAAACUGUCAUUAAAUCGACAAUUUUUUGACGAACGUUGGUCAAAGCAUCGGGUGGUUAGUUGUUUGGAUUGGUCAUCUCAGUAUCCGGAGUUACUCGUGGCUUCCUAUAACAACAAUGAAGAUGCCCCUCAUGAGCCUGAUGGUGUGGCCCUUGUAUGGAAUAUGAAAUACAAAAAAACUACCCCAGAGUAUGUGUUUCACUGCCAGUCAGCUGUGAUGUCUGCCACAUUUGCAAAAUUUCAUCCAAAUCUUGUUGUUGGUGGUACAUAUUCAGGCCAAAUUGUGCUUUGGGAUAACCGUAGCAAUAAAAGAACUCCAGUGCAAAGAACUCCACUGUCAGCAGCUGCACACACACACCCUGUAUAUUGUGUAAAUGUUGUUGGAACACAAAAUGCUCACAAUCUGAUUAGCAUCUCUACUGAUGGAAAAAUUUGUUCAUGGAGUCUGGACAUGCUUUCCCAUCCACAGGAUAGCAUGGAGUUGGUUCAUAAACAGUCAAAAGCAGUAGCUGUGACAUCUAUGUCCUUCCCUGUUGGAGAUGUCAACAACUUUGUUGUUGGGAGUGAAGAAGGUUCUGUGUACACAGCAUGCCGCCAUGGCAGCAAAGCUGGAAUCAGUGAGAUGUUUGAGGGGCAUCAAGGACCAAUCACUGGCAUCCAUUGUCAUGCAGCUGUUGGAGCAGUAGACUUCUCACAUCUUUUUGUCACUUCAUCGUUUGACUGGACAGUAAAGCUUUGGACAACUAAGAAUAACAAGCCUUUGUAUUCAUUUGAAGAUAAUGCAGACUAUGUUUAUGAUGUUAUGUGGUCACCUACCCACCCAGCCCUGUUUGCCUGUGUGGAUGGCAUGGGGAGAUUGGAUUUGUGGAAUCUCAAUAAUGACACAGAGGUACCAACUGCCAGCAUUUCUGUGGAGGGUAAUCCUGCUCUUAAUCGUGUGAGAUGGACCCAUUCUGGCAGAGAGAUUGCUGUGGGUGAUUCUGAAGGACAGAUUGUUAUAUACGAUGUGGGAGAGCAGAUUGCUGUUCCCCGCAAUGAUGAAUGGGCACGGUUUGGCCGAACACUUGCAGAAAUUAAUGCAAACCGAGCUGAUGCAGAGGAGGAAGCAGCUACCCGAAUACCUGCUUAGUUCCUGAAAAGGGGAGUGUAACUAGUGGAUUUGGGAAAGGUUCUUAAGUAGAUCCUGAGACUAUUUGCAUGCUUCUGUCUAAAUGAUAAUUAAAAGGAAAUUUCAUGGAUUAAACCAUGGGUUUAAUGCAGCAAGGAAACUUACAAUGUCCCUUUAUAUAUAACAUGCAUCUUGUUUUGGAUUUGUGUCAUUUUUUAAUAUAGCUGAUUGACUUCACAGAAAGCAGCUUUUUUGAAUUCUAAUACAUAGGUGUAUAUUUGGUAUUAGUUAUUUUGAGUUCUUUUCAACUUAUAACACUGUAUACAGUUAUUUCUAAAGCACAGAUGAAAUAAGUUCUGCAUAUUUUUAAAUAAUCACAGUUCCCUGUUAUACAGAUAAUGUUCUCACUACCCAUAAUAUGUAGGAACAUUGUUUCUCCUUAGCCGUAGUAUGCAUACACCUAUCCAUGUUCAUUCUGACAUCCUUUGUUGUCUUUAUAAUUCAUGUGGUAGUUACCUAUAAAUAAAAACAAAUAUGCGUUAACUUUUCAAAUUUUCAUUUUUACUCCUUACAACUUGAAUUUUUCCAUCUUUUAUAAAAUAUAUUUUUUCCAUAUCUUUCUUUAAGCUCCUGCUGUGAGCAGCCAUCUCAAAUCCUAUAGAGCUGUGUACCCUAAAUAUACCAUGUGGUAUAUACUAUAGAUCUCCCAGUGCAUUAUGAAUUGAUGUCUAGAUAAUCUGUUGGUGAAAAAAUUUCCCCUAGGUUAACUUUUGCUUUACUACUUUAUAUUCUUUCCAUCUAAGACAUAUUUCCUUUAAAGGAUAAAUAGAAAGCUGCCUAUAAUUUUCACUGAUUAAGAACUAUGUAUGUGACCUCACUGAGAGUAAAAUCUUUGAGAGAAAUUGAUUUCAUGAUUUCAGUAGCCAUAAAGGCAAAGUGCUCAAAUGGACCCAUACUUUGGCAUUAAAAUCUACAUCUUGAGAUCUGUUGCCACAGCAUUGUCUACAAGUCCGAAAGGUAGGUGACAAAUAUCUAAGAAUCAGUAUUGAAAUCAGUGAAUUUCAGGAAUAGAGGAAAGGACUAUGAUCAGAUCUUGAUUUUAUCUACUUUAAAUUGUCUAUUUAUUUGAUCCCAACCUUUUGUACUUCUGAAGUGUAACUGUCUUUUAUUCAACAGAACAUGAACUAGGAAGAGAGAUUAGAAAACAGAAUGUGAACAUUUUUCUUUUAAUAAUUGUAACAAAGAUUUGUUGGGAGAGAAAUUUCCAAAUAAUGAGUAGUGUAUAGUGUAAGGAAUAAUUGACCUGGAAUUAUUGGCCCCAAACUCUGAUUCUUGCUGAAGCAUCUAUGAGAAGUGUGAUUUUAGCCAAGUCUGUGCCGCAUUCUUUAUAUGUAGGAAUUAAGUUUUGAUUUAAUGAUUUCUGAAUUUUCUUUCAGCUCUACUCAAUUAAGGGGUAUCAGUAUGUGAAAUGGAAUAUAGAAAAGUAGGCAAUUCUUUACUUUUCUAUAUUCAGUUUCAUAAAUUAAUACCCCAUAAUUGCCCAUUAUAUACCAAAGACAAUAUCUCAAGUUAUCUCAUUGUAGCAGUGUCUGUGAGUCAAAACUUCAAUUUUAGUAGAGUCACACUUUCUUUAUAUAGAAAAAUUCAUGUACUCACUACUCAUGUAGUUACUGUAUCUUUACCUUCAGUUUGUAAAAAUGACUAAAAGUAGGGAAAACAAGUGUUAAAACAUAAUGGAUAAGAAAAGGUUGGAAAUCAUAUGGCAAAUCACAUGUUCCUCAGCCUCAAGGUGUGUUUAGUUGUGAAAGAAAGAAUAAAAUUGUUUAAAUAUUUCACUUUUUGGGAAUGACUUCUCCCCUACUCCCCCAGAAAAUGCGAUGUAUACCUUUGCCCAUUCAACUUUAGUCCAUAUUUUUAGGAACACACAAAUUUACUUUAAGGAAUUACCUUUAAAGUUGACUAUAUAAUAGCAAAAGAGAAAGUAUUGAGACUGUCAGUGUUGAUAAAGCUUCUAGCAAGAUUAGGUUGACUAGAAGUGCAUCACAGUUCUUUAUACUUUUAGAACUAAAAGCCUUAUAAUUUUGAAAAAUAUCCAGUUACAGAAAUUGUACCUUAUCAGUUAUACUUUUUUUCUGAGUAAGAAAACAAGCUAUAGCUUUCUGGUUAAUUUCUUAUUUUUCGUUGUUUGGUUUUUGUCUUUUUGAGUGGAACGUUAAAGUUUAUUACCUUCAUGUUAAGGAAUAUCCAGCUUCACAGACAAUUAACUUGCAAUAAAUCUCUGAAAUAAUCA